GUGACACAGCGAAGAUGGCGUCGCCCGGCUGCCUGUGGCUCUUGGCUGUGGCUCUCCUGCCAUGGACCUGCGCUUCUCGGGCGCUGCAGCAUCUGGACCCGCCGGCGCCGCUGCCGUUGGUGAUCUGGCAUGGGAUGGGAGACAGCUGUUGCAAUCCCUUAAGCAUGGGUGCUAUUAAAAAAAUGGUGGAGAAGAAAAUACCUGGAAUUUACGUCUUAUCUUUAGAGAUUGGGAAGACCCUGAUGGAGGACGUGGAGAACAGCUUCUUCUUGAAUGUCAAUUCCCAAGUAACAACAGUGUGUCAGGCACUUGCUAAGGAUCCUAAAUUGCAGCAAGGCUACAAUGCUAUGGGAUUCUCCCAGGGAGGCCAAUUUCUGAGGGCAGUGGCUCAGAGAUGCCCUUCACCUCCCAUGAUCAAUCUGAUCUCGGUUGGGGGACAACAUCAAGGUGUUUUUGGACUCCCUCGAUGCCCAGGAGAGAGCUCUCACAUCUGUGACUUCAUCCGAAAAACACUGAAUGCUGGGGCGUACUCCAAAGUUGUUCAGGAACGCCUCGUGCAAGCCGAAUACUGGCAUGACCCCAUAAAGGAGGAUGUGUAUCGCAACCACAGCAUCUUCUUGGCAGAUAUAAAUCAGGAGCGGGGUAUCAAUGAGUCCUACAAGAAAAACCUGAUGGCCCUGAAGAAGUUUGUGAUGGUGAAAUUCCUCAAUGAUUCCAUUGUGGACCCUGUAGAUUCGGAGGACCGCCUGGGGCUAAAGGAAAUGGACAAUGCAGGACAGCUAGUGUUUCUGGCUACAGAAGGGGACCAUCUUCAGUUGUCUGAAGAAUGGUUUUAUGCCCACAUCAUACCAUUCCUUGGAUGAAACCCGUAUAGUUCACAAUAGAGCUCAGGGAGCCCCUAACUCUUCCAAACCACAUGGGAGACAGUUUCCUUCAUGCCCAAGCCUGAGCUCAGAUCCAGCUUGCAACUAAUCCUUCUAUCAUCUAACAUGCCCUACUUGGAAAGAUCUAAGAUCUGAAUCUUAUCCUUUGCCAUCUUCUGUUACCAUAUGGUGUUGAAUGCAAGUUUAAUUACCAUGGAGAUUGUUUUACAAACUUUUGAUGUGGUCAAGUUCAGUUUUAGAAAAGGGAGUCUGUUCCAGAUCAGUGCCAGAACUGUGCCCAGGCCCAAAGGAGACAACUAACUAAAGUAGUGAGAUAGAUUCUAAGGGCAAACAUUUUUCCAAGUCUUGCCAUAUUUCAAGCAAAGAGGUGCCCAGGCCUGAGGUACUCACAUAAAUGCUUUGUUUUGCUGGUGAUUUAACCAGUGCUUGGAAAAAUCUUGCUUGGCUAUUUCUGCAUCAUUUCUUAAGGCUGCCUUCCUCUCUCAGUACGUUGCCCUCUGUGCUAUCAUCUUAUCAUCAAUUAUUAGACAAAUCCCACUGGCCUACAGUCUUGCUUCUGCAGCACCCACUUUGUCUCCUCAGGUAGUGAUGAAUUAGUUGCUGUCACAAAAGGAGGGAAGUAGCACCCAAAUUAAGUUGCUUAAGAGAGGAAAUGUACAUCUUGUAUAACUUAGGGAGCGAAGAAAAUGUAGGCGCGAAAGUGAAAAGUGAGGCAGCUAGUUCUUCCUAUUCCAUUCUCGACCAACCUGCCCUUUCUUAAUAUGACUAGUGGUCUUGAUGCUAGAGUCAACUUACUCUGUUGCUGGCUUUAGCAGAGAAUAGGAGGAACCAUAUGAAAAAGAUCAGGCUUUCUGACUUCCAUCCCCAAAACACAUUUACCAGCAUACUCCAAACUGUUUCUGAUGUGUUCCAUGAGAAAAGGAUUGUUUGCUCAAAAAGCUUGGAAAAUACUACACACUCCCUUUCUCCUUCUGGAGAUCAACCCACAUUAGAGUGUCUAAGGACUCCUGAGAAUUCCUGUUACAGUAAACAAAACUAACGUAAUCUACCAUUUCCUACACUAUUUGAGCAUGGAAAUCAUAGUCCCCACUCUGUGAAAACUUAACGCUUUUUGGAAGACAUUUCUGUAGCAUGUCAGUUUGGAGAAAUGAUGAGCUACGCCUUGAUGAAAGAACCGUGUUGGUGCUGCUAAGUUUAGCCAUUAUGGUUUUUCCUUUCUCUCUCUUAAGCCUUAUUCUUCAACUAAAAGAUGAGGAUUAAGAGCAAGAAGUUGGGGGGGAUGUGAAAAUAAUUUUAUGAGGUUGUCUAAAAUAAAGAGUAGUUUCUUAUCCUUGGUGUUUUCAGUAUUUUUUGCAUUUCUGUACAGCCAAUAUCACAGGUAAACAACUAAGCAAGUUUGGUAUUAACUUUAUUCUAUUUUCUGUAUAACUUUAAGUACAUAAAGGUUUAUUUCCACAGGCCUCAGGAAAUGGGUAGAAAUCACAGGACAAUCUCUCUUCCCACCAAAAAAAAGUUGCAUAUUUUGGUAAGUGUUUGUCCUAGAGGGAAAAACAACUGAAAUUUACAUUAGCAGUGCUGUGCAAGAUUCUUACAUAAUUCAAGACCUAAAACCAGCCUGCAGUGGAGGUUUCAGUCCUCUGUUCAGGUGCUUAGACAGAAGCCAUAAGCUGAUGAGCAUGACAGGGAAAAGGAGGCAGUGAAGACAGGUGACAGGCACCUGGCAGGGAAGAAGGAUUCAGGAAUGCCAGACUCCUUGAAAUCAUGUGGGUUUUUUUUUUUUUUUUUUUCCUUUUAAAGUCAUCUCUAUAGGAAGGUGCUGGGCAGGGAUCCCAGAGAAAGAAAGGGUCCAAGACUCCAUUAACUGCCCUGGAUGAAGGGCACUGCUACAGCAGCUAGUACCAGAGACUCUCCUAUCUCACGGUUGAGGCAGACCCAGGAUAGAAUAGAGAAUAAAAGGAAUGCUUAUAGGAAACAAUUUUGUAUGGAAUGCUAGAUGGCCAAGCCUCAGCCUUUGGUCCAGUGCAACCCUUGCCUCGCUUGUCAACAGUGAAAAAUUAGUUUGGUUAGAAGAACCAUCUGGAAACACACCAGCUUCUGCUACCUUCAUGCUCAUUGUUAAAAAAAGAUUAACCAGUGUGAACAUUCUGAUCUGUUAAUUCCAGGGACUGUUUUCUUUCCAAUGGACUGUUUGUUGGUAGAAUAACCCCCAAAAGCUCAAAGCUAAAAUGCAUCAUCAGUCCUAGUCGGCAGUUCCUUAAGAAUGGACUGGCGGCGUGGUUGAGCUGAUAUGGAAAAGCUGCACCUUCCUGCAGAAGAUCAACUGACCUGCUAUCCCACCCCAAAUUUCAGCCUGAGGUAUAUUUCAGUGAAGGCAGGUAGCUGUGCUUCUCAGAGCAGAGAAGCAGUUUUAAGAGCAAAAAGGUAGAGGAAAUCUAGAAAAGAACCGUCUUGAUACAGAUUUAUCCCAUGGUGUGAAGGGAGGGCAAAGAACCCAGUGGCACUUCGCUUAUCCAGCAAUUUCUGUCACUGUGGUGACCAACUUCUGCCCGUUCCAUAGGGUCUUGAACUGCUCAGGAACU